AGCAAGCGGCUGAUUGUUCGGCUGCGAGGUCGGCGGGACUCUUGCUGCGCGGAGGAGCCGUGCGGAACCCGAGGCUGCGCGCGCGCGCGCGCUCUCUGGCCGCGGCGUGGGGACAGCGAGGCGCACUGGGGCCUCCCAGCGCGGGGCCGGCCGCGCCGUCCAGCCCGAGGUCUACGGCUUUGCGCUCCGAGCCCAGAGGAAGAUGCCUGCCGGCACCGAGCUCGGGCUGCGGGGCUGAACGCCUGUCUUCCAGGCGCAGCGGCAGCACUGCCCUCGGCCGGUGUCGGUAGCGGCACUCGGCGUGCCCCGGGCGGACGAAGAGCGCAGGCUGGGUACACCUUGCCCGAAUCGGCGGAGUUCGCAGCUAGCGCGGGCGGGCCGGCCGGCCCGGAUGGGCGCGGGGUUUGCGGCCCCCGCCGGGUGCUCCGGAGCGGCCCGGGCACCGGGGGCACGCUGAGUGCCGGAGCCGCGGCCGCAGAGAGAACUUGGGGCGGGGGCCAUGCCCCGGUGCGGAGUCUAGAGCCGAGCGGAGCGCCCCGCGGGCCCGCCCGCGUCUGCGGCCGUUCGGGUCCUCACAGUCCCCGCGCCCGGAGUUCGCAGCGCGCUCCAGACAAGAUGGCGCGGCCGGUCCGGGGAGGGCUCGGGGCCCCGCGCCGCUCGCCUUGCCUUCUCCUUCUCUGGCUGCUUUUGCUUCGGCUGGAGCCGGUGACCGCCGCGGCCGGCCCGCGGGCGCCCUGCGCGGCCGCCUGCACUUGCGCUGGGGACUCGCUGGACUGCGGUGGGCGCGGGCUGGCUGCGUUGCCCGGGGACCUGCCCUCCUGGACGCGGAGCCUAAACCUGAGUUACAACAAACUCUCUGAGAUUGACCCUGCUGGUUUUGAGGACUUGCCGAACCUACAGGAAGUGUACCUCAAUAAUAAUGAGUUGACAGCGGUACCAUCCCUGGGCGCUGCUUCAUCACAUGUCGUCUCUCUCUUUCUGCAGCACAACAAGAUUCGCAGCGUGGAGGGGAGCCAGCUGAAGGCCUACCUUUCCUUAGAAGUGUUAGAUCUGAGUUUGAACAACAUCACGGAAGUGCGGAACACCUGCUUUCCACACGGACCGCCUAUAAAGGAGCUCAACCUGGCAGGCAAUCGGAUUGGCACCCUGGAGUUGGGAGCAUUUGAUGGUCUGUCACGGUCGCUGCUAACUCUUCGCCUGAGCAAAAACAGGAUCACCCAGCUUCCUGUAAGAGCAUUCAAGCUACCCAGGCUGACACAACUGGACCUCAAUCGGAACAGGAUUCGGCUGAUAGAGGGCCUCACCUUCCAGGGGCUCAACAGCUUGGAGGUGCUGAAGCUUCAGCGAAACAACAUCAGCAAACUGACAGAUGGGGCCUUCUGGGGACUGUCCAAGAUGCAUGUGCUGCACCUGGAGUACAACAGCCUGGUAGAAGUGAACAGCGGCUCGCUCUACGGCCUCACGGCCCUGCAUCAGCUCCACCUCAGCAACAAUUCCAUCGCUCGCAUUCACCGCAAGGGCUGGAGCUUCUGCCAGAAGCUGCAUGAGUUGGUCCUGUCCUUCAACAACCUGACACGGCUGGACGAGGAGAGCCUGGCCGAGCUGAGCAGCCUGAGUGUCCUGCGUCUCAGCCACAAUUCCAUCAGCCACAUUGCGGAGGGUGCCUUCAAGGGACUCAGGAGCCUGCGAGUCUUGGAUCUGGACCAUAACGAGAUUUCGGGCACAAUAGAGGACACGAGCGGCGCCUUCUCAGGGCUCGACAGCCUCAGCAAGCUGACUCUGUUUGGAAACAAGAUCAAGUCUGUGGCUAAGAGAGCAUUCUCGGGGCUGGAAGGCCUGGAGCACCUGAACCUUGGAGGGAAUGCGAUCAGAUCUGUCCAGUUUGAUGCCUUUGUGAAGAUGAAGAAUCUUAAAGAGCUCCAUAUCAGCAGCGACAGCUUCCUGUGUGACUGCCAGCUGAAGUGGCUGCCCCCGUGGCUAAUUGGCAGGAUGCUGCAGGCCUUUGUGACAGCCACCUGUGCCCACCCAGAAUCACUGAAGGGUCAGAGCAUUUUCUCUGUGCCACCAGAGAGUUUCGUGUGCGAUGACUUCCUGAAGCCACAGAUCAUCACCCAGCCAGAAACCACCAUGGCUAUGGUGGGCAAGGACAUCCGGUUUACAUGCUCAGCAGCCAGCAGCAGCAGCUCCCCCAUGACCUUUGCCUGGAAGAAAGACAAUGAAGUCCUGACCAAUGCAGACAUGGAGAACUUUGUCCACGUCCACGCGCAGGACGGGGAAGUGAUGGAGUACACCACCAUCCUGCACCUCCGUCAGGUCACUUUCGGGCACGAGGGCCGCUACCAAUGUGUCAUCACCAACCACUUUGGCUCCACCUAUUCACAUAAGGCCAGGCUCACCGUGAAUGUGUUGCCAUCAUUCACCAAAACGCCCCACGACAUAACCAUCCGGACCACCACCAUGGCCCGCCUCGAAUGUGCUGCCACAGGUCACCCAAACCCUCAGAUUGCCUGGCAGAAGGAUGGAGGCACGGAUUUCCCCGCUGCCCGUGAGCGACGCAUGCAUGUCAUGCCGGAUGACGACGUGUUUUUCAUCACUGAUGUGAAAAUAGAUGACGCAGGGGUUUACAGCUGUACUGCUCAGAACUCAGCCGGUUCUAUUUCAGCUAAUGCCACCCUGACUGUCCUAGAGACCCCAUCCUUGGUGGUCCCCUUGGAAGACCGUGUGGUAUCUGUGGGAGAAACAGUGGCCCUCCAAUGCAAAGCCACGGGGAACCCUCCGCCCCGCAUCACCUGGUUCAAGGGGGACCGCCCGCUGAGCCUCACUGAGCGGCACCACUUGACCCCUGACAACCAGCUCCUGGUGGUUCAGAACGUGGUGGCAGAGGAUGCGGGCCGAUAUACCUGUGAGAUGUCCAACACCCUGGGCACGGAGCGAGCUCACAGCCAGCUGAGCGUCCUGCCCGCAGCAGGCUGCAGGAAGGAUGGGACCACGGUAGGCAUCUUCACCAUUGCUGUCGUGAGCAGCAUCGUCCUGACGUCACUGGUCUGGGUGUGCAUCAUCUACCAGACCAGGAAGAAGAGUGAAGAGUACAGUGUCACCAACACAGAUGAAACCGUCGUGCCACCAGAUGUUCCAAGCUACCUCUCUUCUCAGGGGACCCUUUCUGACCGACAAGAAACCGUGGUCAGGACCGAGGGUGGCCCUCAGGCCAAUGGGCACAUUGAGAGCAAUGGUGUGUGUCCAAGAGAUGCAAGCCACUUUCCAGAGCCCGACACUCACAGCGUUGCCUGCAGGCAGCCAAAGCUCUGUGCUGGGUCUGCGUAUCACAAAGAGCCGUGGAAAGCGAUGGAGAAAGCUGAAGGGACACCUGGGCCACAUAAGAUGGAACACGGUGGCCGGGUCGUAUGCAGUGACUGCAACACCGAAGUGGACUGUUACUCCAGGGGACAAGCCUUCCACCCCCAGCCUGUGUCCAGAGACAGCGCACAGCCAAGUGCGCCAAAUGGCCCGGAGCCGGGUGGGAGUGACCAAGAGCAUUCUCCACAUCACCAGUGCAGCAGGACUGCCGCUGGGUCCUGCCCCGAGUGCCAAGGGUCGCUCUACCCCAGUAACCACGAUAGAAUGCUGACGGCUGUGAAGAAAAAGCCAAUGGCAUCUCUAGAUGGGAAAGGGGAUUCUUCCUGGACUUUAGCAAGGUUGUAUCACCCGGACUCCACAGAGCUACAGCCUGCAUCUUCAUUAACUUCAGGCAGUCCAGAGCGCGCGGAAGCCCAGUACUUGCUUGUUUCCAAUGGCCACCUCCCCAAAGCAUGUGACGCCAGUCCCGAGUCCACGCCACUGACAGGACAGCUCCCCGGGAAACAGAGGGUGCCACUGCUGUUGGCACCAAAAAGCUAGGUUUUGUCUACCUCAGUUCUUGUCAUACCAAUCUCUACGGGAAAGAGAGGUAGGAGAGGCUGCGAGGAAGCUUGGGUUCAAGCGUCACUCAUCUGUACAUAGUUGUAACUCCCAUGUGGAGUAUCAGUCGCUCACAGGACUUGGAUCUGAAGCACAGUAAACGCAAGAGGGGAUUUGUGUACAAAAGGCAAAAAAAGUAUUUGAUAUCAUUGUACAUAAGAGUUUUCAGAGAUUUCAUAUAUAUCUUUUACAGAGGCUAUUUUAAUCUUUAGUGCAUGGUUAACAGAAAAAAAUUAUACAAUUUUGACAAUAUUAUUUUUCGUAUCAGGUUGCUGUUUAAUUUUGGAGGGGGUGGGGAAAUAGUUCUGGUGCCUUAACGCAUGGCUGGAAUUUAUAGAGGCUACAACCACAUUUGUUCACAGGAGUUUUUGGUGCGGGGUGGGAAGGAUGGAAGGCCUUGGAUUUAUAUUGCACUUCAUAGACCCCUAGGCUGCUGUGCGGUGGGACUCCACAUGCGCCGGAAGGAGCUUCAGGUGAGCACUGCUCAUGUGUGGAUGCCCCUGCAACAGGCUUCCCUGUCUGUAGAGCCAGGGGUGCAAGUGCCAUCCACACUUGCAGUGAAUGGCUUUUCCUUUUAGGUUUAAGUCCUGUCUGUCUGUAAGGCGUAGAAUCUGUCCGUCUGUAAGGCGUAGAAUGAGGGUUGUUAAUCCAUCACAAGCAAAAGGUCAGAACAGUUAAACACUGCCUUUCCUCCUCCUCUUAUUUUAUGAUAAAAGCAAAUGUGGCCUUCUCAGUAUCAUUCGAUUGCUAUUUGAGACUUUUAAAUUAAGGUAAAGGCUGCUGGUGUUGGUACCUGUGGAUUUUUCUAUACUGAUGUUUUCGUUUUGCCAAUAUAAUGAGUAUUACAUUGGCCUUGGGGGACAGAAAGGAGGAAGUUCUGACUUUUCAGGGCUACCUUAUUUCUACUAAGGACCCAGAGCAGGCCUGUCCAUGCCAUUCCUUCGCACAGAUGAAACUGAGCUGGGACUGGAAAGGACAGCCCUUGACCUGGGUUCUGGGUAUAAUUUGCACUUUUGAGACUGGUAGCUAACCAUCUUAUGAGUGCCAAUGUGUCAUUUAGUAAAACUUAAAUAGAAACAAGGUCCUUCAAAUGUUCCUUUGGCCAAAAGCUGAAGGGAGUUACUGAGAAAAUAGUUAACAAUUACUGUCAGGUGUCAUCACUGUUCAAAAGGUAAGCACAUUUAGAAUUUUGUUCUUGACAGUUAACUGACUAAUCUUACUUCCACAAAAUAUGUGAAUUUGCUGCUUCUGAGAGGCAAUGUGAAAGAGGGAGUAUUACUUUUAUGUACAAAGUUAUUUAUUUAUAGAAAUUUUGGUACAGUGUACAUUGAAAACCAUGUAAAAUAUUGAAGUGUCUAACAAAUGGCAUUGAAGUGUCUUUAAUAAAGGUUCAUUUAUAAAUGUCA